CUCCGCCUGGACGCAGCAGCCACCGCCGCGUCCCUCUCUCCACGAGGCUGCCGGCUUAGGACCCCCAGCUCCGACGUAAGUCCCUCUCGUGCGCCACCUCCAUCCGCUGCCCCUCUGCCCACGGGCCGGGCUCAGAUGUCGCCCUCUGGUCGCCUGUGUCUUCUCACCAUCGUUGGCCUGAUUCUCCCCACCAGAGGACAGACGUUGAAAGAUACCACGUCCAGUUCUUCAGCAGACUCAACUAUCAUGGACAUUCAGGUCCCGACACGAGCCCCAGAUGCAGUCUACACAGAACUCCAGCCCACCUCUCCAACCCCAACCUGGCCUGCUGAUGAAACACCACAACCCCAGACCCAGACCCAGCAACUGGAAGGAACGGAUGGGCCUCUAGUGACAGAUCCAGAGACACACAAGAGCACCAAAGCAGCUCAUCCCACUGAUGACACCACGACGCUCUCUGAGAGACCAUCCCCAAGCACAGACGUCCAGACAGACCCCCAGACCCUCAAGCCAUCUGGUUUUCAUGAGGAUGACCCCUUCUUCUAUGAUGAACACACCCUCCGGAAACGGGGGCUGUUGGUCGCAGCUGUGCUGUUCAUCACAGGCAUCAUCAUCCUCACCAGUGAGAACUGGGGUUGGGUGGGAAGGACACCAAGACCAGGAGGGGGACUUAUGACGGAGGGCUGGGUUCUCAAAGGUCCCUGGGCAAUUUUGUUUUAAAUGAGGUAUCUAUUAGCUGCAUAUACAUACAAACCACCACAGAAUUCAGUGGUUUAAAAUAAUGACCAUUUAUUGAGCUCUCAAUACCACAGUUUGGAAACAUAGGCUGGGCUCAGCUGGGUGAUUCUUCUGGUCUCAACUGGAUUUACUCUUGCAUCUGAGUUCAGUUGUGGGUCAGCAGGAAACUUUGUUUCUGGGGUGCCUUGGCUCUUUGCCACAUCAUCUUAUCCUUCACUAAGCUAGCCUGGGCUUGUUCGCAUGGUGGUGGCAGGGAUCUAAGAUAGAGUGAAUGCAUGCAGGCUCAGAACUGGCCAUUAUCACUUCUGCCUCAUUCCAUAGGUCAAAGCAAGUCAUGAGGCUGGGUUUCAUUCAAGGAAAUAGACUCCACCUCUUGAUGGGAAGAUAGGCAAAGUCACAUGGCAAAGGACAUGGAUACUGACAGGGAGGGGUAGAGACUAAGGGCCAUUUGGCGGUCAGCAUACCACCCCAGCAGUCACAAGCCCACUGCACCCAGGCCUGGCAGGGAACAAGGGCUGAAAAAGGCUGUGUCAGGAGGAGAUAACUGAGGAUUAAAUGCCUCAUGGAACAACCCCACCCACUCAAUCCAGCAAGAAUAGAGGCUUGAAGCAGCCAGAGUAACUACUCUUUUAAGAGCUUAAUGUUUCUGUAAAAUCUUUUGGUACUCAAAUGUUGACAGCUGUGUUGAUCAGGGUCAUGGCAGGUGGCAGAAGGACCUGCAAACGAUUAACUGGAGAAAGUUUAAUAGAGUGAUAUCUCUGGAGGUACAGGCAGGGCAAUGAGAUGGUGCAGUGCCCUAGGACUAGCAAGGAUGGGGACCUGUUAUCCCCCAGCCUGAGGGACAAGAGGAGGCACUGGCUUUGCAGGAGGCCUGGUGAGAGAUGGAACUGGAGGUGGGGCUGCUGGCAGGAGCUGUGGCCUCAGAAAGAGGGUUCCAGCCACUGCCUCACUUGUGACCAAACCAGGAGGGAGCAGGGGUGGUGGGGAUCAGAUACCUAAACCUCCCUCUCCUCCCACCCCCCUGUCUCCUGCCAAUGCUUAACCAGAGGGCAAGGGGCCCAGGGCCCCAUGCAGGGAGAGGAAGUUGUGGGGAAAGGCAGAAUAACAAGCAGAGAAACUAAUUUUUUAAAAAGGUUUUUAAAAUGUUGUGGGUGAAAUAAAACACGAGCUAUCAGUUAAUCUGUAUAACCAA